CGGCCUUCCCCCGGCUCCCGCGCUCCCGAGCUUCCACCACAUCGGGCCCGCUCGGAGCAGGGAGUGCUCCGAGGCGUCAGGGCCCAGGGCCCACGAUCCUGGGACGCCCUCCGGUCCUCCGCCCUGUCGCGGAGGCAGCGUUUUGGAUCCCUCGCCGCACAGGGGCUCCUGCGAGGCCCCCUCUUGCCCCACCCACCCAGAGCCGUCAGGGCUGGCCGAAGGCGAACAGCCGGCCCAGCCGCGCGGGGCCUUUCUCUCACAACGCCCCCACCACGGUCGCUUGUCCCGACCAAGACCCGGCCGGGGGGCAAGAGGGCGUGGGGUGUAGCGGGUCGGGGGGUGGCCCUGUUUUGCCCCGGGCUGGCACUAGAGGCGGCGGCCUGAUCUCGGGUGAGAGGGCCUGAGAGAAACCCAGACACACCCCACCGCCACCAGGAGCAAAUCCACUCCCCCACACACAGACACACCCGUUCGUUCUCGUUCCGGAACCCGCACGCGAGCACGGGUGCGCAGACGCACGCACACACACACACGGUGAAACACAGACACACACGGCUUGAAGGAGAGCAAGGAGAAGAUGGAUGGAGAGAUAGAAACCGAGGGAGGGAGAGAGACAGCGAUCGAGAGAGACCGGAGAGGUGGAGAGGUAAAGAGAGAGAGGCUAAGAGGGACAGAGAAAGGGAGAAGUACAGAGGUACAGAGGGAAGGCUAGAGAAAUAACGCGAGGUCCAGGGGGAAACCAGAAGAGUGAGGAGGAGGGAGCUAGAGAGCGAGAACGUUUGAGCCUUAGAGAGGAAGCACCCUACUUCGGUAGGCAGCCCCCUUUUGAGCAGACCGGAAUAGGGUGGAGGGGUUUGAGCUGUGCCUGAGCAGGGCGGCCAGGCGGCCCGUGCGAGAGGACCAACGGAGCGCUGAGACGGGUUUUUUCUUGGAUGAAUUGCUUGCUUUGGAGGUGGGUUUCGUAGGCUCCAUUCUUUCUUGGCACCUCAGUGUGCUCUUGGUACCUCACUGUGCUCUUGGUGCGGUGCAGUGGGCCCCGAGAUUUGCAGAGUGCGCCCGCCCUUUUGGCGGGAGCCGUGGUACCGGGCGCGUCCGGAGGCCUGGGUCUCUGGCGUGUCCUCGGUACUGGAGUUGACACGAAGUGCGGGGCAAUAGGAAUCCGGGUGCACAGGGACUGUUUUCCUGGUGGUUGGCGAAGCAAUGUCCUUCCCCCCGGGUAAAGCAGUCCAUGCGUUCUGGAGCGGAGAUCUUGGCUGGCGUCUGUGGUACCCGCUGCCCCUGCCCGCCCCUUCCCCCGGUUUAUAAGGUUGCGACUGCGCCGGAUGAGUGAAUUGAAUUGCCUGGUGGAUCCGGGAGCGGGAAGGCACCGCGAACGGCAGGGAAUCCUGGCCUGCACCUUAGUGAUCUGAGGCGUGGUGUUUCUGCUGGAUCCGGUUUCAUCGUGUUGCGCCGCCCAUCCUGAAUAGUUGUGAUGUUGUUGCCUGGCUGUGCUGCAGGUUAGCCCACACUAAGCGGUCCCGGGCUGUUGUGUGGGCUUGGGCGUGUGAAAAGAGGGAGCAGAUUUACGGUGCGGUUGAGAAGUACGGCGACCAAACGGUAAAGAGGGAGGAACUUGAAGUCUAAACAAGCCUGCGUCUCUUGGUUUUCUCAAGUGGCGUUUCAUCUAAGUAGCGGUCUGGCCCAGACCCUGCUUAUCUUCACGAGAUCAGAGGAGACCGGACGCCUUCGGGGUGGUAUGGCCUUAGACGCCGGUAGUGCAGCCUGUCUGCCCCAAAGGCGCGGCUCAGCCACGCCCGUCCGACUCCAUGCGCCACCUCUAAUCCAGUGCCAUGGGGAUCUUAUCGGGACCCGGGAGCCGCUCGCCGGAGGUCUGGCUGGGUUGCUCUCCGUGUCUACGCCCAAGCACCGUUGCCCGCCGCCUUGCGCCUUCUGUUGGCCUCUUAGAGCCUUCCGUGAUUGCUUGCGCCUAGGCCACUCGCUGGACCUCCGCGGCGCCACCCUGUUUCCUCGCGGGAGUGCCAGAGGCCUUUUCCCCUGCCCAAGCUCUGGGAUCUCCGGGCAGCCUCCAUUCCGCCGACUCUCCAGGCCUUCCCCGGCUCCGGAGCUCCAGAGCUUCCAUGACUUUGGGCCGCUCCGGACUUGGUGUGCUCUGAGGUGUCAACGCCCAGGGCCCACAGUCCUGGGAUCUUCUCUGGUCUUUUGCCUUGCGGCGGGGGGAUUGUUUUGUAUCCCUUGCUGCCCCUCUUGCAAGACCCUCUCUUGCUUCACCCACCCAGAGCCGUUUCUUUAAAAUUUCAACCAUGUUCUGAACUGCAGCUUUACAGUUGAAUAUUUUCUUUCAGAAUAAUUUGAUUCUGAACUCGGUUUUUCUUGACAUACCUGAAUUGUUUCAUGUGAGCCGGCAAUUUCACAUGCUUUUACUUUUUCUUUUUUUUAAAAUUUUUAUUUUUGAGACAGAGUCACAUUAUAAUCUAUUACUUCUACUAGAGAUCUGUUUCUUCCUAUUUAAUGAAUUAUUGCUUUUCAUAUAGUCUGAAAUUUGUUUUUUCUCUCUUUCUUUCUCUUCCUCUCUCUCUUUCUUUCUUUCUUUCUUUCUUUCUGACGGAUUCUCGCUCUGUUGGCCAGGCUGGAGUGCAGUGUUCGAUCUCGGCUCACCGCAACCUCCUCUUCUGGGUUAAAGCCAUUCUCUCGCCUCAGCCUCCCGAGUACCUUGUACUAAAGGCGCGCACCAACCUCGCCUGGCUAGUUUUUGUAUUUUUAGCAGUGACAUGGUUUCUGCACGUUGGCCAGUCCUGUCUCAAACUCCAGACCUCGGGUGAUCUGCCUGCCUCGGCCUCUUAAAAUACUAGGUUUACAGGUGUGAGCCACUGUGCCUACCAGCUUUUACUUUUUCUAAAAGCCAUGUAUUACCCUGUUCAAGGUACUAGAGUACCUGUUUACAUUCCUCUAUAAUAUGGCAAACAUUACUAAUUUUGGGCACACACUCUUCCUUUGUCUUAUUGAAUUCAAGUACCUUUUCGUCAGGUUUGACUUCCAGGUUCUCUAAAUGUGCUUUCUGGAGGCUGAAGCAAUCAUAUUGCUGGAGAUAUUUCUUUACCUUUUUGAUAACUGGUCUAAGAAACAAAGAUUUUACAUUUUAUCAGGAUAAUUAUCUGUGGUUCCUGUUGCUUGUUUUUAUUAGGUUUUUGAUUACUUGACAAAACAGCGCUUAAAAGGGUUAAGGGUUUUUAAAAAAAUUCAUGUAACUGUCUGUAUUUCAUUUUGAAGUAUUUUGAUUAUCAUCCUGGUUAAAUAAAUGACUAUUAAUUCACAGUGACAUUUGAUGCUGUUUUGAUAAAGUGUUUUUAACCUUUUGAUAUUUUGGCAAGCUUUCCCGGGAUCACAUCCUAAAUUGUCUUUUCUUUUUUUAUCUUGAAUUAACUUGAUGUUCCAGAGGGCCCUGAAACUUUUCAAAUGUUUAUAAAAGAGACAUAUUAAACUAAAUCAGGCUCAUUUGAAGAUGAUAAACUGUAUGAAAAACAUUGUCAAAUAAGUUACACUAGAUCUUCUUUCAGUUAUAUUUUAUGGGUGUGUUAUUGAUAUGAAUGUUCCAAAAUUGUGUAAAACUCCUAGAAAUCUAAGACGUCAUCAGUUGUAAUUCUGCUUAUGUUGUUUGACACAAAAUAACCAGUUUCUUGUCAAUUUCUGGUUAUAAUAAACUUUCAUCAGAUUUUUAACCAUAA